ACUGCUCAGUAGAAGCCAUGGCUCGCAGACACUGCUUCUCCUACUGGUUACUGGUAUGCUGGUUGGUGGUAACUGUGGCAGAAGCACUGUCCACUUUCUAUCUCCAGCAGCAUAUUAAUUUGCACAUGGACAAGAAGAGGUAUUUACGCCUCCUGGAGAUUCACAAAAUAAUGCGGACGCUACCGACUGCCAGAUCUUUACACUCACCCCUCCACCUGCCCCGAGGAGUCCGGUCACAAGGGCCCAGCCCAUCACAAAGACACCCAGGUGUCCCUUCCAUUUUUUUCCACGAAGGCCCAGAAUCCAUUUUAGGUUUCCAAACAGACCUUUCGUCCCUUCAAGGUGUAACCACCGUUUUCCAUUCCAGCCAUUUUAUUGGCCACACCGUUACCUUACUUAUAGGUAUUUCCCCAGAAGAAGACUCCAGAGAGGAAGCUCAUCUGAGGAAAGCUGAGAGGGAAGAGAAACCCAAACAUACUGAAGCAAAAAAAAGCCUAUCCUUCAGAAAAAAGCAACAAAAAGAUUUCUGUUUUAUCUUUCGAAACUAAAACUAUUGGAUUUGAAGAUUAAGUAUCCUAAACAUCACUGACUAGAAACUGUUCUCUUUGUCAGCAGUGAAGAUAUUGGAUCAUAGGUUAUUGAUGGUUGCAAAAUUGGACAAUAACCACGUUAUUUUUAUCCUCAACCUCUUAUGGUCACAGGAUAUUUAUGCAAAUAAAAUCUUUAAAUGGGUGGCUCUAGUAAUUCCUAUCCAUACUAAGAUGCUGAGAGAAUCCAUCUCCUCCUCUAAAUUAAACAGGAUUUAAAUAAAUUGAGAUCAUUAUAAACCACACGAAGAAACUGAUGACACCGUUUUUAUACUCAUUGGAAAACAUACAGAGCAAGGUGCAUUGACAAAGUAAACUUUAAAAGAAAUUAUAAAGCUUAAAGCAAUUAAAAAGUUAUGAGGAGUCUGACUGUAGCUAAUACUUUAAAGAUAUAAACUGACUUGUCUAACCCAAAUAAUAAUAAUUAUUAUUAUUUUCUUGGAGACAGAAUUUCACUCUUGUUACCCAGGCUGGAGUUUAGUGGUGCUGUCUCGGCUCACUGCAACCUCUGCCUCCCGGGUUCAAGCAAUUCUCUUGCCUCAGCCUCCCAAGUAGCUGGGAUUAUAGGUGCUCGCUACCAAGCCUGGCCAAUUUUUUGUAUUUUUAGUAGAGAUGGGGUUUCACCAUGUUGGCCAGGCUGGUCUCGAACUCCUGACCUCAGGUGAUCCACCCACCUCGGCCUCCCAGAGUGCUGGGAUUACAGGCAUGAGUCACUGCGCCCAGCCCCAAAUAAUUACUUUUAAACUAUAGUAUCUAAAUUUACUUUAAUGUUGACUUCAACUGAUGCAAAUUAAUUUGAUAAUUUUCUCACUGUUUCCCGUUAUCAUUACAUAGAUGCUGGCUAAAAUAAUAUACUUCCUCUCAAACUUUUAACGUAAUUCCAGGUUCAAAAUGCCUGAUUAAACUGCUACAAGAAUAUUCUGGUACCUCUAGAACUCCACAGAGAUAAGUUCACUCAACUCUUGGAACCUUGUAUUCUCAGGGUGCAAUAUGAGAAACAAAUCCCACAGAUUGCAUUGAUUGGUUAUUUGUUUUGGCCACUCUGUAAAACACAUCUUCCUGUUUAUGCCACUUAUCUUGCCUGUAACAUAAGAACUUUAGUUCUGCAUAUGUGGUCAGUGGUUUGCACUUUUUCCUCCCAAGAUCUACAUGCAAAAGUUGCUGUUGCUGCUGCUGCUACAAAAACAGAAAAAAAAAAAUCAGGAUGAAGACAUGAAAGGACUUUGGGAAUGGUUGCCCUAAAAAAGGAAAGAGAGAUAAAAUCAUCAUGCUAUGUUUCUUUGCUUUAUUAAAAUGAUCAAAAAAGAAAAAAA